AGUAACACCAGUUGUAAACCCAAGGCCAAGAGACCAUGGCCACGUUAGCCCGGCUGCAAGCUAGGUCGUCGACUGUAGGAAAUCAGUACUACUUUAGGAACAGUGUUGUAGAUCCAUUUAGAAAAAAGGAGAAUGAUGCAGCAGUUAAAAUCCAAAGCUGGUUUCGAGGAUGUCAAGUUCGGGCAUAUAUCAGGCAUUUAAACAGGAUUGUAACAAUUAUUCAAAAAUGGUGGAGAAGUUUCUUAGGCAGAAAGCAAUAUCAACUAACUGUGCAGGUAGCAUAUUAUACUAUGAUGAUGAAUCUCUACAAUGCAAUGGCUGUCAGGAUUCAGAGACGAUGGCGAGGCUAUAGGGUUCGGAAGUACCUCUUUAAUUAUUAUUAUUUGAAAGAGUACCUGAAAGUCGUUUCAGAGACCAAUGAUGCAAUUAGGAAGGCACUGGAGGAGUUUGCAGAAAUGAAAGAAAGAGAAGAGAAGAAGGCUAACCUCGAAAGGGAAGAGAAGAAAAGAGAUUACCAAGCCCGAAAGAUGCAUUACCUCCUCAGCACAAAGCAGAUUCCAGGAAUAUACAAUUCACCCUUCAGAAAAGAGCCUGAUCCAUGGGAGCUGCAAUUACAGAAGGCAAAGCCUUUAACACACCGAAGACCUAAAGUUAAGCAGAAGGACUCCACCAGCCUUACUGAUUGGCUAGCUUGUACAAGCGCCCGUUCUUUUCCUCGGUCUGAAAUUCUACCACCUAUUAAUAGAAAGCAAUGUCAGGGGCCCUUCCGAGAUAUCACCGAAGUAUUAGAACAACGCUACAGGCCUUUGGAGCCAACGUUGCGGGUGGCAGAACCAAUCGAUGAGUUAAAGUUGGCCAGAGAGGAGCUCAGAAGAGAGGAAUGGCUGCAAAAUGUAAAUGACAAUAUGUUUUUGCCAUUUUCUUCAUACCAUAAAAAUGAAAAGUACAUCCCAUCAAUGCAUUUAUCAAGCAAGUAUGGUCCUAUUUCUUACAAAGAACAAUUCCGAAGUGAAAAUCCUAAGAAAUGGAUCUGUGACAAGGAUUUCCAGACUGUAUUACCAUCAUUUGAGCUCUUCUCAAAGUAUGGAAAAUUAUAUUCAAAAGCUGGACAGAUUGUAUAAAGAAAACAGAAGAUGAAAUGUAAAACUGAGAUUAAGGUGUGAAGUGAGUGUGAAUAGAAGACCCCACACUGCCUGGAGUCCUGGAUUCUUCCACGUCUGAUGAGUGACCUUGGAUCUCUUAAUCUCUCUAGUUUUCUCUCUCUUAGGCGUCAGAAGAAGAAACUGAAGCCAUCUGCAUUUUAAAACUUAACAGUUCUGAAAGGAAAACACAGAUGAAGAUCCUGUAGGAAAUAUACUUGCUAUGAUUCAAUAAACUAUAAAAUUUUGUAGCUCUAGUCAUGAAUUAAUUAUUGUGUGUAUGUAUUUGAAAUCUCUUAGACAUAUCUUUUCAAACAAAUACUUAAACUUGAGUCUGUUACCUCUGAGAAUGUCUGUCACAAUCACAGCCCCUGGUGACCAACAGUGCCAUAAAUGGUUCCCCUGAAAUACCCAUAUUCUGACCCCAUCACCCGGGUCACAAAUGAUGACACCAGUGCUGGGUACCCAAAUUAAGGGCGACUAACAUGUAAGUAGGAUGAUGAAUGGUUUGAAGUGUAAAUUGUGUGAAAUAGUUCAGCAUGAAAGCUCUGCCCUGAGAAAUAAUGACUGAUUAUACCAGUUAGAAACCCUUCAGACUGUUGAACUUGAGACACACAGACACAACAGACACAGACUAGUGGGUGUGGGAGCAGAAGCAUAGGCACUCUCAAAUAGAGAAGACAUUUGCAAGUCUCUGCUGCCAAGGGAGCAAAGAGAUAAUCUCGAUGCCAGGGCUGUGUCAGAUCCUGCAUGGCUCUGAACUACAGUUGGUUUCCAAAAAGCUGGGCUUUUGUGAGGUUUCUGUUUUUUAUGCGAUGCUUAGAUUUUCCUGGAAUCCUUGGAAGUUAACUCAACAUUUGAGGUUCCUAUAUCCUUUAAUCCCAUCCCAUGUGUAUCUUUACAAUAAAACUUCCUGCUAGAGGUAUCCUGAGGGAAUCUUUGUUUCUUGCAUCUGAAGAGAAUAACACUAAACUUAUUGCAUAUGAUUUGGGGGUUGGAUCCAAUGAUAGCACAGAGGGACAGGAAAUGUGAUUUAUUGACCAUAAAAGCUUUAAUUUAAAAUUGCUGGCCAGCGAAAUCCAGACUCUGGGAAAUGUUAUAGGCCAAAUGAUCUGUUUCUUCAACAAAUAAAUUACAAAACUGAGGGGAAAAAAAGGAACCUAUUAAAAAGACAUUAUCUAUCAAUCACUGUGUGUGUACAGUUUUGAGCUCCUGAUUUAAAUAAACAAAUUGUAAAAUAAAAGAUCUUUUGAAACAAUUGGAAGUUUGAACACUGAUUGGAUAUUGGUGGUAUAAAAGAAUUAUUGGUUUUUUUUAGGUGUCAUGGUAUUGUUUUGGUUUACAAAGUUAUAGAUAUAAAUGUUGAAAUAUUUACAGAUGCAGUGAUAUGUUGGCUGGGAUUUAAUUUGAAAGUCAAAGAAGUGAGUUAAAAUACAUAUACUCCUCCUCUUAUAAUCGGUUAUGUGCCAAUAAAUCCAUUGUAAAUUGAAAAUAUCCUAAGUUGAAAAUAUUGUAAGUUAAAAAUGCAUUUAAUACAGCUAACUUACCAGACAGCUUAGCUUAGCCUCACCUACCUUAAAUAUGCUCAGAACACAUACGUUAGCCUAUAGUUGGGCAAAAUCAUCUAACACAAAGCCUAUUUUAUAAUAUUGAACAGCCCAUGUAAUUUAUUGAAUAUUGUACUAAAAGUGAAAAACUGAAUAGUUGUAUGCAUACUCAAAGUAUGGUUUCUACUGAAUGCAUUGUAAACCAGAAAGUAUCUGAGACAAUGUUUUUUUUUUUUUUUUUUUUUUUUUUAAUUUCUGAGACAGAGUCUCAUUCUGUCACCCAGGUUGGAGUGCAGUGGCAUGAACUCAGCUCACUGCAACCUUCACCUCCCAGGCUCAAGCAGUCCUCCCAUCUCAGCCUCCCAAGUAGCUGGGACCACAGGCAUGGGCCAACAAGCCUGGCUAAAUAUUUUGUACUUUUGGUAGACACGGGUUUUUACCAUGUUGUGCAGGCUGGUCUUGAACGCCUGAGCUCAAGUGAUCUGCCUGCCUCGGCCUCCCAAAGUACUGGGAUUACAGGCAUGAGUCACUGAACCCAGCCCUGAGACAUGUCUCAAUUAGUUUAGAAGUUUAUUUGGCCAAGGUUAAGGACAUGCCCUUGACACUGCACCUGUCAGUACAGGUCCUGACAACAUGUGUCCAAGGUGGUCAAGCUAUACAACUUGGUUUUAUACAUUUUAAGGAGACAUAAGACAUCAAUAAAUACAUGGAAGAUGUACAUUGGUUCAGUCUGGAAAGGCAGGAUGCCUCAAACUUGAAACAAGAGAAUGGGGGGUGGGAGGAUGUGGGAGAUGCUUCCAGGUCAUAGUUGGAGUCAAAGACUUUCCAAUUGGCAAUUGGUUCAAAGAAUUUAUCUAAAGACCUGGAAUCCAUAGAAGGCUUUACCUGGAUUAAAAUAAGGGGACCAAGGUUCUCAUGCAGAUGAAGCCUCCAGGUGGCAGACUUCAGAGAGCAUAGAUUGUAAAUGUUUCUUAUCUGACUUAAAAAGGUGUCAGACUCUUAGUAAAUUAUCUCCUGGAUCAGUGAAAAGAUGUGAAAAAAGGUUCUCUACAGAAUGUAGAUUUUCCCCAUAAGAGAUAGCUUCGCAGGGCCAUUGCAAAAUAUGUCAAAAAUAUAUAUUUUAGGGUAAAAUGCCUCAAUUUAUUUCAAGGCCUGAUAUUUGUCAUGUGAUGCUAUACUACAGUCAGGCUGAAACUUGGCAUCUUAUUGCUAUGAAAAAUCUUAAGAUCUCUAUUUUAAUGUUAAUGCUGGUCACUGGUGCCUGAAUUCCAAAGGGAGGAGGGUAUAAUGAAGCAUGUCCAAUUCCCCAUGCCCCACCCCCACCCCCACAUCCUAUAAUGGCCUGAACUAGUUUUUCAGGUUAACUUUGGAAUACCCUUGGCCAAGAAGAGGGGUCCAUGCAGAUGUUUGGAGGGGGGGGUCUUAAAGCUUUAUUUUUAGAUUACAGCAUAUUGCUUUUGCACUAUCAUAAAGUAAAAACAUCAUAAGUCAAGCCACCAUAAAUAGCGGACCAUCUGUAUAUCUGAAAGAAGAUGAACCAAGACUUGGUUAUUGUUAAAGCUGAUGAUUGGCUGUAUGAAGAUUUACUAUACAAUUUUGUGUACUUUUGUAAGUUCUUGGUUGUUUCUAAACUUAUAACAAAAUAAAUAAUUGGCCAUCUUCAUUGGAUUGUGAAGCCAUUUCCUCCCACAUGUUCGUAAAAAUGGUAGCCAUGGCCCCUGACUGAACCCAGGUAUGAAUGGCCUUCAUUGAUUUUGUAGACCCUGACCUUCUCUGUUCUUCCAGAGAAGGUGGUACUCAGAUAAAAACUUUGAAGCAUUUUAUUGUUCAGAAUAUGACUUUGAUCUUCUCAUAAGACUCAAGUUUUUGAAUGCUUAAGGCUCUUUAUCGCUAGUGUAUGUAAGUAAUAUCAUUGUCCUUAACCACCAUCUGCCUCUCCCCCCAGACACACAUAAGUUUAUGAUAACUACAGAGGUGUCCAGAUGAGUAAAAACUGCCUUUGCAUUAAGGUGAGAGAAGACCGAGAUGAAAUCUUAUUAGAAAAUAUAACUGGGGAAAGCAGUUUGUCUGUUUCUCCUGGAAAACUACUAGACUACAUCAACUUAUAUACUACUUCUUUUCUAUAUUCUCAAUAUGAGCCACUUAAGAAAAUUAAUGAGACUUUAUGUUUGACCAAAGCUGGUAAUUCCUUGAUCUUAUUCUCCAAACUUGAUUCUGAAUGACUACUGACCACUAAAAACACUAAGAGUACCACUGUGGAUGUUUAAAAACAUACACCCUAAGAGCCUUCAGAAUUAGACGCUUCAAUUCUUCUGAAAUCAAAAGUCACACCAGCUUUGCUGUAGUUAAUCAGGUAAUACCUUUCUUCUCCACUACUCUCUAAUUUCCUUGAGGGCAAAUAUUGUCUUUCUUGAUAAAUGCCCUGGACCCAACAUCUAACAGAAUACCUGGCAUAAAGUGAAAUCCAUCGAAUGUGCUAAUGAUAAAUAAAGAAGUUCAAAAAAAUCUUUUAAUAGAAGCUAUAAAAUAGCAGAUAAGCUAAGUCAUUCUCAUAAAACACCAUUUGUCAUUUGAAUGCGUGCAUUGUGGCCUGUUACUUUUAACUAGUCUCACUAAUUUAUAGUUAUAUAUGAUGUAGAUCUAGAUUGUGAUGUACACUAAGUGGGUUGAUCCUGAGAUCAAGCUAUGAUUGCUGCUUGCGUAAAGUGUUCCUUUUGGGAAAUAAAUAAUCUUUCAUAUCUGUAAACUUUGGUAUAAUUGGUUAUUUAUGCAAUGUAUUGUUGUGGUUGUCAACUCAAGAUUGUAUUCUCAUCUGGGGACAUUAUGAAUCUUGUUAUUUUAUCCCCUUUUUUGCUCUGUUUUUUCACAUUUAUGGCCUACCUGUUACAGCUGCACGGUAUCCAUUUUCUGUGCUAAAUUCAUCUUUAAUUUAUUAUUUUUUUUCAACCUCAGCUUUUAACUUUGCCCUGAUUUUCUCUUCCAUUUUAUUUUCACUUCCAUUUUAAGCUGGCUCAAAGCCUUUUAGGAACAAUAAGUUACUGAAUUAUAUGAACCUAUUUGAGGUAAUGAUGAUGCCUGGGAAGGAGCAGUAUUGCUGGAUCAGAAUUCACUUUUUCCAAGUUACAGAUUUUAAUAAACCACUGUGCAAAGCAUUAGGAUAAAUUUUUAUUGAAAAUUGAGUGAAUGACUGAACAAAUCGCUGGGUAAUGCUGUUUAGGUUGUUCUAUUUUCCACGGAUUAAAUUAAAUUCUAUGUA